AGCUGGCUUGGACCCUGGCGGGGCGGGCUGUGGGCCGAGCGGCGGAGCCCAGGCGCCAGCCCGUGGCCGAGAAGAAAGGUGGCGGUGGCGGCGGCGGCGCAGCGGACGGGACGGGGCGGCGGCUCCUCGCCCUGACCCUCUGCUCCCCCGCCCAGGCCCGGGCGCGAAUCGGAGGCUGCGGCGAAGGAAGGAGUGAGCAUGGCUGAGACCCCGCCGCCGCCCACCGCUGGUGCCGAAAGUUGCAGCGAGGAGCCGGCGAGGGGCGGGGAGUGGCGGCCGGAGGAGCCGCGCCGCGCUCCCGCCGGGGGCACGGACCGAGAGGGCGAGGCGGGGCCGCCGCCGGCCUCCCCCGCCGGGCAGUCGGAGCCCGACUCGCCGGUGGCCGCCCCCUUCUUCCUGCUGUACCCCGGCGAUGGAGGCGCCGGCUUCGGAGUGCGCCCGCCGCCGCAGCAGCAGCGCUCCUGGAGGACCCCGCCGUCCCCCGGCUCACCGCUGCCCUUCCUGCUGCUGAGCUACCCGAGCGGCGGCGGCGGCAGCAGCGGCAGCGGCAAGCACCGAAAUUUCAUGAAGAGACUUUGCGUGUGUGUGUGUGUGUUUGUGUGUGUGUGUUUUAAAUGUCUUUUUAUUUUCUCUGAAUAAAAUUUAACAUCCGGGGAUGAGGAAGAGUUAGGAUAGAGUGCUGAAGUUGCAGAGUGUAGAAGGAACAUGGACUUUGGAGGUAUCUAGACAGAAGUAGCUUGGAGUAACAGAUCUGCUACUCGCUAAUUGUGUGAUUCUGGGCCAGUUACGUGGCUGAACUUUGGUUUCAUUGUGUAUAAAGAGAAGGUAUCAAUCUCUGUUUUGCAGUGCUUUUGUGAAGACUUGACAUGGUAUUUUUUUUUUUUUUUUUUUUUUUUUUUGAGACAGAGUCUUACACUGUUGCCCAGGCUGGAGUGCAGUGGCGCGAUCUUGGCUUACUGCAACCUCCGCCUCCCGGGUUCACGCCAUUCUCCUGCCUCAGCCUCCUGAGUAGCUGGGAUUACAGGCACCCACCACCAUGCCCAGCUAAUUUUUUUGUAUUUUUAGUAGAGACGGGGUUUCACCGUGUUAGCCAGGAUGGUCUCAAUCUCCUGACCUCGUGAUCUACCUGCCUCGGCCUCCCAAAGUGCUGGGAUUACAGGCGUGAGCCACCGCACCCAGCCCUUUACAUGGCAUUUGUAAAGCACCUAACAGAAAAUAGAAAUUUAAUAAAUGAUAGCUAUUUUAGGUAAUUUUUCCACAAUAUAUAACAGAGACAUUGAGCCUGUCAAGUUAACCUUUGUCUUAUAGUAGCAGCCGAGUACAAAUAUCCUUUAAGAGGAAUGUAACUUCUGACUUUGAAGUGUGACUCUUAUUUGCUUUGAAUCCAUCAUAAUGUGGAAAAUACAGACUGUUUAAGCAGCUAGAACGUAGUAUUUUUUGGAUCUUCAUUUUGGAUUUGAACUUCACACAGGCCUAUUCUUUUAGGGCCACAGACUGAACUCCCACCCGCCUCACAACCAUCUUACAAAUAGGUGCCAUUACUCACAAAUGGGAUCAAAUGAGAAAAUAGUUCAAUACAGCUCAUACAGUAAUUACUCUGUAUGUGAGAAAAAAAAUCAAGGUUUGAAUAUCUUACUGAUGGCUUAACUUUAACUUCAUAUUCAAAGCUAAGAUGUUUACUUAGUAAAGACCAAAAUGUAAAAACGGUACUAAGCAAUAUCUAAAAUCUUUUUUUUUUUUCUUUGAGACGGAGUUUCACAGGCUGGAGUGCAGUGGUGCAAUCUCACCUCACUGCAACCCCCGCCUCCCAGGUUCAAGCGAUUCUCCUGCCUCAGCCUCCAGAGUAGCAGAUUACAGGCAUGUGCCACCACGCCCAGCUAAUUUUGUAUUUUUAGUAAAGAUGGCGUUUCUCCAUGUUGGUCAGGCUGGUCUUGAACUCCCGACUUCAGGUGACCCGCCUGCCUCAGCCUCCCACAGUACUGGGAUGACAGGCAUGAGCCACCGUGCCCGGCCGUAGAAUUGUUUUUAUAAGUUUCUACAAAUAGCACUGUUUUCAUAGUAACUUCUUUGCCUGUGAACAAUGGAUAACUGUUCGUGCUGAAGACUCAAUGGUGUUUACCUAAAGAACAGCGUAGAAGUACAGUUUUUCUUGCCCACCCCCGGGUCUUAUUUCUGAAAUGGCUGCCAACACCUCAAACUGGUAGAUCUGGGAAAUUCAAGGAUACCAAUACAGGCAUGUUUUUCUUUCCUUGCCAAAAACUUUAGUUGUUUUGGGCUUGCCUCUCUGUGUCCUCUACCUGGAGAGAGGCAGGGUGGGAUGGAUCUUCCGAAGGAAUGUUAAUCAAGUUUCUUGCUCACUAACCUUGAUGUUCCUGUUGUGUUGGUAUGUUGCAAUCAAUCUAGAUCUGUUCAAGUUAGUAAAUGCUUACUGGGGUGAAGAGAUUGUUGUGGUUUGUGACAAGGCCAAAUUCAGGUUUUGGACCCCAGACAAUCACAUGGCAUUCGGAUUUAUUCAUGUAUUCCUUGUUCUGUUUUAAGAACAUAUCAGUGAUCUAGAGUUUUGAUAUCACACAUACAGAUAGCUAGGGCUGUUUGGAGUUGUGGUUCCAGGAAUGUCCCAUGUAAUUUGAAGGUUUUAAUGACUACUUACUAUGUUUUGAAGUAUUGCAUGAUAUAAAGUGAAUCUAUAAACUGUCCCCUUAUUAAUAUAUAAUAUGGGAAUAUUUUUGGCUAGAAAGGAAUUGAACUGAAUUAAAUGAGAAUGUGUUAAAUGAAGGCUUGUGUUCAGUAUUUGGAUAUGAAAAUUCUGUUUCCUGGAAAAGGUGUUUCUGUCUUACUGCUGCGUGCCUAGUGCCUGGAUCACUACCUGGCAUGUGGAGCACCUCUUAGUGAAUAUCUGUUGAAUGAAUGAAUGAAUGAAUGGCUCUGAGUCUAGAUGUAGGGUAAUGAUGAGAGAGAAUGAGAUAGAAAUAAAACCAGGAGUAUUUUGCUUUCCUUAGUAACUUACUGAUUUUCCCCAAUUAUAAAUAAGCCUAUAUAUAUGCCUUCUUACAUUGUACCAGUAUACCCUCCUUCUUUUUUUUAUUUUGAGACAGGGUAGAGUGCAGUGGUAUGAUCUCGGCUCACUGCAGCCUCUGCCUCCUGGCCUCACGUGAUUCUUCCACCUCAGUCUCCCAAGUAGCUAGGACCACAUGUGCGCGCAACCAUACCUUGCUAAUUUUUGUUUUUGUAGAGAUGGAGUUUUGCCAUGUUGCCCAGGCUGGUUUCAAACUCCUGAGCUCAAGCCAUUCACCUGCCUCAGCCUCCCAAAGUGCUGGGAUUACAGGCACAUGCCACCACAUCUGACUAAUUUUUGUAUUUUUAGUAGAGAUGAGGUUUCACCAUGUUGGCCAGGCUGGUCUCGAACUCCUGACCUCAGGUGAUUUGCCCGCCUUGGCCUCCCAAAGUGCUGGUAUUAUAGGCAUGAGCCACCGCGCCCAGCCAUCCGCCCUGUCUUCGUAACAAUAUGAAAAUGCCAGUUUCUCUACAGAAUUUGAUUAUUAGCAUUUUUUUCUUUCAGUUCAGUCUCAAAUUAUGAUGAAGCAUUUGAGAUUUUAACAAUAUUCAAGGAGAAUUUUUUUAGUUUUCAGAAAUUAGGUAAAUCAAGAUGUCCCUCUGAUAACAAUCCCUAGAAAGGAAUAGUCUCAGGUCAUAUUUCUUGAAUUUGUAUGUUCCUCCUUAAAAUUGGAACCCUUCAAUACAAAAACAAACAAACACUUUCUUUCAAUUGUCCAAAACAUUUUCAAAGAAAAUUCUUAUUCUUCUCUUUGUAAUUUAUGUAGUUCAUAAAGCAAGUACCUGCCCUUUUGCUACCAAGGUAUAAAUGCCUCAUUGGAUAAUAUAGGGCCGUGUGUGUGUGUGUGUGUGUGUGUGUGUGUGUGUGUGUGUGUGUGUAUUAAGAAAAUAUAAUUGUCUUCAGUAUCUUAUCGAAUGGGAGGAUUUUAAAAAUAUAACAUGGUUUAAUCUGCUUAGAAACAUAUUUCAUGCUUAAGGCUGGGCAUGGUGGCUCACGCCUGUAAUCCCAGCACUUUGGGAGGCUGAGGUGGGAGGAUCAUGAGGUCAGAAGUUCAAGACCAGCCUGGCCAAGAUGGUGAAACCCCGUCUCUACUAAAAAUACAAAAAUUAGCUGGGCGUGGUGGUGGGUGCCUGUAAUCCCAGCUACUCGGGAGGCUGAGGCAGAGAAUUGCUUGGACCUGGGAGCUGAGAUCACGCCACUGCACUCCAGCCUGGGCUACAGAGCAAGACUCUGUCUCAAAAAAGAAAAAAGAAAAAAAAAGAAACGUAUUUUAUGCUUAAUACAGAAACUUGAUAAAUACAACAAAAUCAAAAAGGGGGGAAAUUGCCAUUAAUUGGGAAAGAUUUUACUUUUUUAACUUGAAGUUUUUUUUUUGCAUUUCUGCCUAACCUAAAAGGUCAGGUUUUUGUACCUUGGAGAAGGAAAUUAUAAAUGCCCAAGAAUAAGAUAUUUAAAUUGAAAAUCUACUUUAGCUUUUCUUUUUAUCUUUUUGUUUUUUUUCCCUCUGAGAACCUCAAUUUUUUAUGCUUUAGCUUUUCUUAAAACAUAACAUUUAGCAUAGUAAAGAAUUUUAAUAGCUAUGUAGAUAAGAAUGAAAGAGGUGAAUUAUAUGCUUGUUAAAUUAAUCUAACUGCCUCUUUUACCAUCUUUACUAUAGAUUAUUAUCCGGUAUUAAUUGUCAUCCUUUUAUUCAGUCCUUGAUCCCAAAGUAAGAAGAAUUGAUGAGGAUAUGUGCAUUGUGUUAUGUCUGAUCACAGUUUGACUAGCACAGUCUGGAAGUGGGUUGUACAGGAUGAGAGAGAGAAGCCUAAUUGCUCUCCCAGCAUCAGCAGCAUCUAUAAAGCAUCCUGGGAAUUGCUUGCCCUACGUUCAGAGCAGCUGGUCACAUGAGCCUGAAUUUUCAGUUCAGUUCAUUAGUCAGCCAUUUUGGUCAACACCCUGCUUACUGCGCACGGCCAAUCCUAUGAGAACUCAGCAUCCCAGCUCAUCUGAGCAGAUCCUGGAAGUGAUUUCUGCAGCUCAGGAUUUUUUUUUUAAGCUACAUUGAAAAUAUAGGUUUAUUUUUUGUUCAGGUUUUUCUUUUAUAUUUUUUUUCUGCACAAAGGAGGAGGAUUUUUCACUUACUCAUAUCGAGGCCAGAUUUUUAAAGCCAGCUAAGGCAGCAUCAGCUGUGCGGGAUUUAAAGCCUAUAGCUCAGCUGAAAAAAAAGGUGGGGGGCAGGGAAGGGAAGAUAAAAGGAGAGGAAGCUGGGAGAAGACAAGCAUCAUCUUAUUUUGCUAUGUGGUAGGAACUGUCUAUAAGAUAGUGUAGAAUUGUUUAUCUUGAGCAGUUUGUUCUUAACCUAUAAGGUAUUUUUCCUUUUUUUUUUUUUUAAACCUCCCCCACCCUUUUCCUGAAAGCUUUGUUUCAGAGCUUUGUAUUGGGUUUUUUUGGUGAGGAGGUUGUAUUUAUUUUUUUGGUGUGUGUGUGUGAGUGUGUGUGUGUCUGUGUGUGUGUUGUGGUCCCAGCUGAGUCAUCAUGUCUGCUCUGACGCCUCCGACCGAUAUGCCAACCCCCACCACUGACAAGAUCACACAGGCUGCCAUGGAGACCAUCUACCUUUGCAAAUUCCGAGUGUCCAUGGAUGGAGAAUGGCUCUGCCUGCGAGAGCUGGAUGACAUCUCACUUACACCUGACCCAGAGCCUACCCAUGAAGACUCUUGGGAGGAUUUGACAGAUUUGGUGGAGCAAAUGCGCGAUGAUACAGAAGAUCCUAAUUAUCUCAUGGCUAAUGAACGCAUGAACCUCAUGAACAUGGCCAAGCUGAGUAUCAAGGGCUUGAUUGAAUCAGCUCUGAACCUGGGGAGGACUCUUGACUCUGACUAUGCACCUCUCCAGCAAUUCUUUGUGGUGAUGGAGCACUGUCUGAAACAUGGCUUGAAAGCUAAAAAAACUUUUCUCGGACAAAAUAAAUCCUUCUGGGGGCCUCUAGAACUGGUAGAAAAGCUUGUUCCAGAAGCCGCAGAGAUAACAGCAAGUGUUAAAGAUCUUCCAGGACUUAAGACACCAGUAGGUAGAGGAAGAGCCUGGCUUCGUUUGGCAUUAAUGCAAAAGAAACUUUCAGAAUAUAUGAAAGCUUUGAUCAAUAAGAAAGAACUUCUCAGUGAAUUCUACGAACCCAAUGCCCUCAUGAUGGAAGAAGAAGGAGCCAUAAUUGCUGGUCUGUUGGUGGGUCUGAAUGUCAUUGAUGCCAAUUUCUGUAUGAAAGGAGAAGACUUGGACUCUCAGGUUGGAGUUAUAGAUUUUUCAAUGUAUCUCAAGGACGGGAACAGCAGUAAAGGUACUGAAGGAGACGGUCAGAUUACUGCAAUUCUGGACCAGAAGAACUAUGUAGAAGAACUGAACAGACAUUUGAAUGCUACUGUAAACAACCUUCAGGCAAAAGUAGAUGCAUUAGAAAAAUCCAACACUAAACUGACAGAGGAGCUUGCAGUUGCAAACAACAGGAUCAUUACCUUACAAGAAGAAAUGGAACGAGUUAAAGAGGAAAGUUCCUACAUACUGGAAUCCAAUCGGAAGGGUCCCAAGCAAGACAGAACUGCAGAAGGGCAAGCACUAAGUGAAGCAAGAAAGCAUUUAAAAGAAGAGACACAAUUACGAUUGGAUGUUGAGAAAGAACUGGAGAUGCAGAUCAGCAUGAGGCAGGAGAUGGAAUUGGCUAUGAAGAUGCUGGAGAAGGAUGUCUGUGAGAAGCAGGAUGCCCUGGUAUCUCUUCGGCAGCAGCUGGAUGACCUCAGAGCUCUCAAGCAUGAACUUGCCUUUAAGCUGCAGAGUUCAGACUUAGGAGUAAAACAGAAAAGUGAACUAAACAGUCGCUUGGAAGAGAAGACUAAUCAGAUGGCUGCUACCAUUAAACAACUUGAACAAAGAUUGCGCCAGGCUGAGCGAAGCCGCCAAUCUGCUGAGUUGGACAACCGGCUCUUCAAACAGGACUUUGGAGACAAGAUCAACAGUCUGCAGCUGGAAGUCGAGGAGCUCACCAGGCAGCGGAACCAGCUUGAGUUAGAACUAAAACAGGAAAAAGAAAGAAGAUUACAAAACGACAGGAGCAUCCCAGGAAGGGGUUCCCAGAAGUCAGAAUCCAAGAUGGAUGGGAAGCACAAAAUGCAAGAGGAAAAUGUUAAACUAAAAAAGCCCCUGGAAGAAAGCCACAGGCUGCAACCCCACCCUAUGGAUGAACAGGAUCAGCUGCUGCUCUCUGAAAAGCCACAGUUGUGUCAGCUAUGCCAGGAAGACGGCAGCCUAACAAAGAAUGUGUGUAAGAACUGCAGCGGAACCUUCUGUGAUGCCUGUUCAACAAAUGAACUGCCUCUUCCUUCAAGUAUCAAGCUUGAGCGAGUUUGCAAUCCCUGUCACAAGCAUCUGAUGAAGCAAUAUUCUACCAGCCCAUCAUAAGACUGGAGGCCAAGACCUGGACCAAAACGUUUAUGCAGGCUCCUCUGUACCUGUGUUUUAGCUGUCAGGAUCUCAUAGAGCCCAGUUCUUAGAGUCAACUAAAGAGUUGAUAGGAAUUUACUAGGUCCAGGGAGAAAAGGCAGUGGUUGGGGUUACUGGAAAUUUUGCUCAUUUUCUCUAAUGACUGUAUGAAUAAAAGUGAACUUACUUGAGCCUUUCUCUUCUAAAUCUAAACAACCUGAUAUUGAAGGUUUGCUUUAUAGCAUAUCUUUGGAAAGGCAACUCAUUUUUAUGAUUAGUGAUACUGGGGUGGAUUUAAUAGGAGAGAGAAUCCAGGCAGAUAAGAAUAAAAAGGAAAAUGAUCAUCUCCUUCUAUAGCAUUUGCAGAUUCAAGGGGGAGAGGUAGAUGCUGAGAUCAAAAUGACAGUUGUUACUUAUUUUUCCAGGUGCUGUUAGUAUAAACAUUGUUUCCUCUUCACCCCUGCUAACUACCUCUUUAAAGUAUUUCUACCAAACUGUGAACCCAAUCUCAGGGAAAAGAAAUUAAAAAGUAAUAUAAAUUCUGCAUAUAUUAAAAACAAUAUUGUAAUAUGUUAUAAUUUCAGGACCAGAAUUUUCUGGUCUUUACCUACAAGGGUUUUCAUUAUCAAAAAAAAGAACAUUUGUUUUUCUACUUUAUGACUUCAAAGUAAAUAACUGCCCUUUUCAGAAUCUCCUUCCACAAAACAAGCCAACUCUUCCCCAUUCCCUCCAUCUUCCUUUCCAAGUCAUAAUGGAAAUUGUAAGGAGUUUUAAAAAUAGGGUUUGGCUUUUGCAAAUAGAAGAUAUUGAUUAAAGCAAAGUCAAAUAUAGAGUAAAAUAAGUUUAAUUUGUUUUCUUAAGACAGGGUCUUGCUCUGUUGCACAAGCUGGAGGGCAGUAGUGCAAUCACAGCUCACUGAAUCCCUGUUCUCCCGGGCCUCAAGCAAUCUUCCCACCUUAGCCUCCCAAGUAGCUGGGACUGGCUUUUUUUUUUUUUUUUUGGCCGGGGAGGGGGUCUCAUUGGUUGCUCAGCCUGGUCUCAAACUCCUGGGCUUAAGCAGUCCUCCCACCUUGACUUCCACAGUGCCGAGAUUACAGGCAUGAGCCACCACACCUGGCCAAGUUUAAUUUGUUCAUGGCUGAGAACAGUUAGCUCGGAAUACUUACAUUGUUUUUUGAAUAAGGAAUUCCUUAUUCUGAGUGAGUCACGAAUGAGAGCUGAUAGAUGCUUUCUUGAAAAGGGCAAUACAGUCAUCCCUUGGUAUCCAUGGGGGAUUGGUUCCAGGAACCCAACUUGAUAUCAGAAUCCAUGGGUGCUCAAGUCCCAUUAUAGAGAAUGGGUUAUAUGGUAUUUGCAUAUAACCUACAUACAUCCUCCUGUGUACUUUAAAUCAUCUGAAGAUGAUUACUUAUACCUAAUAAAAUACCUACACAUCACUUCAUUUGCAUGGAUUCAACAUAGUGCUUGGUGUUCAGUAAAUUCAAGUUUUGCUUUUUUGGAACUUUGUGGAAUUUUUCUUUUUCUGAAUAUUUUUGAUUGGCAGUUGGUUGAAGCCAUGGAUGCAGAACCCAUGGAUAUGGAGGGCUGACUGUACUUACUUACAUAUCUAUCUAUCUUUGAGUAACAAACUCUUUGGGGGAAAAGAGGGAAGUGUAUUGAGCAAGAGAAGGCAAAAAACAUUACAUAAUAUUUUGAUUCUGUUACGUGUGUCUAUAGAUUGUUUCAUUCUAAUCAAGACCUAAGAAGGUAUGAUUCUGUGACUGAUUUAGAAUUCUGGGGUGGAAAUAUCCUGGAACCAUGUUUUUUAAUAAAUUCUGUCUCUUGGAAAGAGUUAACAACAGCCUGGGAAAGAGUUGUUAUUCCAAAAGUCAGCCUGUUACUUGGUGAAGCUGAAGUUUAAGAGUUCUGGGGAAAAAUAAAAUCUAGUAAUUCCAGCCUA